GACAGCGGGCUGAGCCACCGGCUUGGCGCGGCGGCCAAACUGGUGGGACAGUGUCUCCAGGUAGUGAGGCCCAACCUCUUUAAAACAAACAAACAAACAAACAAAAAACCAAAAUGCAAACGUGAGUAGAGAAUGAAAUACACAGUUUAAAUGCCCUCACUAUCUUUGGGUUACUAAUAUACUAAGCCUUUCUGGACUAAGUAAAAGAUGCAGGUUCCUGCGGCUAGGGAUAGAAGCCAGACUGGCGUCUUCAGAAUCUCCCACCAAGGCUGUACCUCUGGAGGAGUUCUAGGUUUGGAUUUGGUCAUCUCAAGAAGAGACUUCAGAUGGAUUUUAAAAUUGAACACACUUGGGAUGGUUUUCCAGUGAAGCAUGAGCCCGUAUUUAUCAGGCUGAAUCCAGGUGACAGAGGAGUGAUGAUGGACAUUAGUGCUCCAUUUUUCAGGGAUCCUCCAGCCCCACUUGGAGAACCAGGAAAACCUUUCAAUGAACUGUGGGAUUAUGAAGUUGUGGAAGCAUUUUUCUUGAAUGAUAUAACUGAGCAAUAUUUAGAAGUUGAACUUUGUCCCCACGGACAGCAUUUAGUGCUUUUACUUUCUGGAAGAAGAAAUGUGUGGAAACAAGAACUUCCUUUAUCGUUCAGAAUGUCCAGAGGAGAGACAAAAUGGGAAGGCAAAGCUUAUCUCCCUUGGAGUUAUUUUCCACCAAAUGUGACAAAAUUCAAUUCAUUUGCAAUUCAUGGAUCAAAAGAUAAACGAAGUUAUGAAGCUCUUUACCCUGUACCUCAGCAUGAACUGCAGCAAGGACAAAAACCUGAUUUCCAUUGCCUAGAAUACUUCAAGUCUUUCAAUUUUAACACACUGCUUGGAGAAGAGUGGAAACAACCGGAAUCAGACCUGUGGCUAAUAGAGAAAUGUGAUAUAUAGGAGUAAUAGAUAACCAUACCGAUCAUUUUUUCCUCUAUACCUUUUAAGAUAAACAAAAAAUAAAUAUCAAUUUUUUAAGAUGUCAUGCAUACAUUUCAACAACAAAUAUCUUCAUAGAAGUCACUGAAAAUAUAGUAUCUGUGGCAAAUUGUAUAUGAUUAACAAGAAAAUAUAUGAUUCUUUGUAGAUGAUUUCAUCUGUAAAGUCACAAUGUUUCUCAGAGUCACUUAGUCCAGGAUGUUGCAUUCCCAGCACACAGUACAGUUAUUCUUGAAAACUACAAGUGAAAAAGGGGGAACAAUUGAGGUUGUCCAAGGCCACCUAGAGGACUGUCUUGCACUACCUUGUGAUUCAACCAUUUCAUUCCUAGAUAUAUACCCCAGAAAAAUGACUGCUCAUAGCAGCUUUAUUCAUAAUAGCACAAAAUUGUAAACAGUGAAAUUUCCAUCCAUAGGAAAAUGGAUAGACAAACUACAAUAUAGUCAGUGGAAUACUGUUCAUUUAAAAAAGGACUGCUGAUACAUGCAACAACCUGUAUGAAUCUCAAAAACAUUAAGUUGAGCAAAACAAACCAAACAUAACAUACUAUCUAAUUACUUUUAUAUUAAAGCCACUUCCAGGCAAAACUAAUAUUUGAUGAUAGAUACCAGAACAGUGGCUGCUUAGAGUGAGGGCAGGGAAUUCAAAUUGAAUGGAAAAGGGGCCUGAGGAAAUUUUCCGGGGUGAUUGAAAUGUUUUGUAUUUUGAUCUGGAUGAUGGUUAUGUAGCUGCAUAUAUUUGUCAACAUUCCUCAUGCUGUAUGUUUAGAUUUGUGAUUUUACUAUAUGUAAAUUAAUUCCUUAAUAAAAUACUAUUAUAAAAUAAGCUGUAAAUUAAAUGGAAUUAACUUCAAGUUUACAUUGAGUUUAUAUGUUUCCAUUGAACAAUCACUAGUGAUGGUUAAAUGUGGCUUAUCGACUUACUCAUUUCUUAUAUAUGUUCUCUAUCUAAAAAGAGAGCUGGUGUAAGAUAAAUGCUAACUUUUACAAAAGGUAUUAUUAAGUAUCCUGACUACACAUCAUGGUGGCAGUGUUAGGCAUCUUAGAUAAAUUGAGAAAUUAUUCUUAAAACUGACAAUAGCAACUAAUUAAUUUGAUAUAGAAACGAUCUGCCUGUUUUAGAUACGAAUGGCAUAUUUUAAAUAACCUAGGACGAUUUAUUUAUAAAUUACCUGAAUAAUUUUAUAAAUGCAUAUAAAACUAUCAAAAUAAAAACAAGAUAUAUUUUAGAGCAUCUUGAUUUUAGAAGCGAAUCGAACACUGUGAAUCACAGUUUCAGAUAUAAAUCAUAACUAUUUAUAAUAUGGAUAAAAAUGAAGCACAAAUAUGAUAGAUACAAUCACAACAAUAUAAAAUACUGAAUUUGAAUGUUGUAGCUUGUGAGCUUUCUCAAAUCUAAUGUGUAUCUUUUUAAAAUUUGUUUAGAUGUUUUUUAAACAUCUCUUAACUUUCUUUCAUCUAGAUAAGGCAUUUCCUUUUCUUCCAAUACCAAGCAAGCAAAAAUACAUUAUAUAAACAUUUUCUUUUGAAAGGAACAUGCAUAUCAACUACAGAAUUUCGGAAAGCUUGUCCAUUAGUCAGGUACAAAUGAUAUAUUCUAGAAACUUGUAUCCAAGAAACUUUUAUUUGAGAGUGGGUGUUUGUAAUAGCCAUUUCAAAUUUGUUUUUCAACUUCAGGACCAUGAAAGAAUAAUCAUCCUUUUGUUUAAAAUAUGCAUAAAUGCAUUUCUUUGCUGUGAUUUGAAUUGUUCACUGCAGUGUCAAGCAGAUUCUCUCUUCUCACCACCUAAAUAGAUUACACAAUGUGCAUAUUUAUUCAGGUGCAUUCUCAUGCUUUUUCCCAGCUCCAGGAAAGUGUAAGUCACAGUCUGAAGGGAAAUGUGCUUUUUAUUUUUGGCUCCAAACUACUUUUUUUAAACGUUAAAAAGGUUUUUUGCCACAGGAAAAAAAACAUUUAAUUUCCCCUCCUUCUCCUCCUUUUGCUCCUUUUUUAAAUGUUAGGCUUUUGGAGGACAGAAGAUAAUGAGCAUAAUUAAUCUGAUAUUGAAAAAGAAAGGGUAGCAAGUGGAUAAAGCAAUUACAGUAAGCCCUCAGCCCUUUUCUCAUGCCUCAAAGCUUAAGGAUUGUCUCUUCUUUUCCAUGUAAAUUUCCAUAAUAUUUUACACAUUGCUUUAUUACAGCAUUUAUUUCACUGGUCCUAGAUAGCUCUUCUGACCCACCUCCUAUCCUCUCAGCCUAACUUUUUACUCCAGCCAUCAGUUGCAUACAGUGAACUGACUGGCCAGUUGCCUCAGCUGUACUGUGUAUGUCUUACUUCCUGCCCCUAGGGCUUCUCUGCUUCCUCUGCUGUGUGGAACACUUGCAGGAACCCAUUUAGCCAUUCUCUCACAUGAACUACCCGGGAUGUGUGAAGGGACUAAAACACCCCAUGGGGCACCUCUUGACCAAAGAGGGUGGGAGUUGAUGGAUAACUACUUCUCUGUUACAUCCCUCAGUUUAACAAUUUAUGGUCCCUUCCACACAGCUCCUCAGAAGUUCUCUUAAAAGGAUUCCACCCUGAUUACCCACAGCAGUGGCCAACUAGUAACACAUUUUUGCAUUAUCUUUCCUUCAUUUCCAUCAUUUUCUGUUUUGCUCUUCCUGGUACCUCUCUCCUCUCUGGAAUUGCUUAACUACAGUCAACCUCUUUGGAAGUUAUUGUCCUAUGUUUGCUUCAUGGGGAACCCAGGCUAAGUCAGUGAUUACCUAAAGCAGCCCUAGAAAGCCGUUCGUCAGGAUGAGAAUCUAGAAUUGUAUCACAGGGCAUUUGGUGACAAGGACCCCAUUGUUGGUGGUAAUGGCUCUGCUAUAAGUAACUUCACAGUUAUUAAAACAGUGGUAGACUGGCUUGAGGUGCAGCUGAGGCACCUGAAGCUAUGAAAGCCAUCUAGUCAUAAUGACUCUUCGUGUCAACUGUUCAGCAGGCAAAUAGAAGCGGGCUACCAUGCAGAGCUAGAGUUAUAACUAUUAAUGGAAGCAGUAUAGAGUAUGUCCUUCCUAGGGGAUUCAUUGAGUCAUCCUUUGGUGUUUCAAUGUCAAGUGGUAAUCUUAAAUGGGCAACUGUAGCAACCACAGCCUGACAAGGUAAAGCAACUAAGGACUCUGACCCUUUGAGGAUAAAGGUCUAGGUCACCUCACCAUUCAAACCACUUGAAACUACUGAAGAGUUUGGCCAAAUGUGAGAGAAAUACAGAAUUUGUGAUGGAAGAGAGAGAUGAUAACUAUCAAUUAUAGACUUGAAAUCAGUUACAGGAGCCACAUAACUUGUUCCACUAAAUCUUUUGCAUUUAGUAUUUGUAUAAUGGCUGCCCACUUCCUUGAAGACUCUGUGACAGAUUGGACUCAAUGUGGAAUGUGUGUGGCUCUGAGUGCUGCAAGGAGUGGACUGUAUUUAAUAUCUCUUGUGUCCUACCUCACAUCCUCUUAGGCCAUUUUUCAAUUCACCCAUUUUACUCUUUGAUAGCACUUUACCUCUUUUGUCCCAUGUAUCUCUAGAUUUCUGUAUUAGUGCUUUUCUGACACCUCAGUUAUGUGGAACACCUGUGGGAAUCUGCUAAUCUACUCUGACGUAUAUGCAAACCUGGAAGUUUGAGGGAAUUGACAAUAGGGACAGGAUUCAGUGGAUAAAUACUCCCCUUUUCCGUCCCUUGGGCAGACAAUUCUGAAGUGCAUUCUGUAUAGUUCCUUAGUGGUCUCCAGUAGGACUCCACUAGGGUCUUCAGUUACCUACAGUACUGAUCAGCUUAAAAAUGCAAUCUUAGAUUGGCUUGCUUUAUUUAAUUUUUCCAAAGUUCCCAAUCCCAUUCCUUAGAAUCACAUUCCAAAAUUAAUGCACUGCACACAACCCUCUGCUUUUGUCAGGGGUAGAAGGGGUAUCCAGCCUAAGGCACCUAAGUCCAAGAGGAAUAUGUGCCUAACAAAUCUUCUAACUAAAUAUAUAUAUAUAUAUAUAUAUAUAUAUAAAAUAUAUAUGUUUAUAUAUAACAUAUAUAUAUAGAGAGAGAGCAUAAAAUGUGCUGUGUAUGUGUGUAGCAUAUUUUUUGUUAAAUCACCAUUCCUGGGCCCUACUCAUUUUCUGAUAAUUUCUUAUCUUAAUUUGCUCUGAAAGAGCAAAACUUAUAAAAUUGACUAUUGUAACUCUAUUUUUUACCAACUAUCAUUUUUCAUGGAAGGAAUAGUAAAAAGAGUUACCUCUGAAGCUAAGAUGACACAUGUAUGAGGAAUAUAGGAAGCCAGAAAUCAUGAAUCUAUGAAAAGUGAGGGGUGUCUGUGCAUAUUUUAUUUUAUUUCAUAAUAAAUAACCAGUAAUUAAAAUAUUCUUUUCCAUGUAAUGGGAUCUACGAGUAAAUUUUUGUCUGAUAUUUAUAAAUCUAAUAUGUAAUAUAAAGGAGAAAUAGGAAAUGCUGUCAAAUGACAUUUCACUUUACUACUUAUUUGAAUUACAAUGAAAUAAUAUAUAGCUACAUCACUGGCUCCUGAGAGAGCUUUGGGUGUUCUGUAAAUUUUUUACUUUGCACUCUUGAAAAAUUCGCAGAGAAUGCAAGGUUUAGUAAAAAUUUAUUUUCUUUUGGCAGCCUAUCACCUGUAAUUUCCGUUAAACAGCAUUUCUGACUCAAUAGUACACUGAAAGCCCAUGUUUGUAAUAAUGCCCUAAAGCACUGCAGUACCUAGAGUAUAUAUUUUGAAGAGAUAGCUUUGCUGAAAUAGAAAACCAAACUGUAAAUUGAAGUCUGAGCAUUCAGAGAAAUAAAAAUUAUGCUAAAAACAAA